AAGUCUCGCGAUAGCCAGCCGCGGCUGCCCUUGCGCUUCCCGAGCUGGCGGGGUCCGUGGUGCGGGAUCGAGAUUGCGGGCUAUGGCGCCGAAGGUUUUUCGUCAGUACUGGGAUAUCCCCGAUGGCACCGAUUGCCACCGCAAAGCCUACAGCACCACCAGUAUUGCCAGCGUCGCUGGCCUGACCGCCGCUGCCUACAGAGUCACACUCAAUCCUCCGGGCACCUUCCUUGAAGGAGUGGCUAAGGUUGGACAAUACACGUUCACUGCAGCUGCUGUCGGGGCCGUGUUUGGCCUCACCACCUGCAUCAGCGCCCAUGUCCGCGAGAAGCCCGACGACCCCCUGAACUACUUCCUCGGUGGCUGCGCCGGAGGCCUGACUCUGGGAGCACGCAAGACAGGAUCUCACUGUGUUGUGCAGGCUGGUCUCAAACUCCUGGCCUCGAGCAGUCCUCACACCUCAGCCUCCCAGAGUGCUGGGAUUAUAGGCAUGAGCCACUGUGUACAGAGAUUCUGGGUCCCUUCUUCCAGCGCCUGCCUCGAAGUCCUCUCUGGAGAGAGCACAGAUGUCCACGCGUGUUCCAGCACAAGGGGGGCAUGCAACAGCUCAGGGUCACGUCCACUUCCGGAGCUGGGUGCCCGGGCCUCGGGCUCCCUGAGAAAGGGCGGACACACCCACCCCGCACCCAGAGGGGCAGGGGCCCUGACACCUGUCCAAGCCCUAAUAGAGUCAUUGUUAAACACUCUGGGUUCGAACCCCAGAACUUGAUUCUUUCCUUGUUCUGUCCUCAGAGGACGGCAGCACCCAGGCCUCAGCUUUCCCACCUGGUAAAUGGGAAUAAGGGCCCCUCAGAGAUGCCCCACAAAGAAAGACGAUUCCACCUCCCUGCAGGCAUCCCAUCCACUCACGGGCAUCGCAUCCACUCGAGGGCACCGGCCUCUGUCUCUACUGCGGCCGGCAGGGGGCAGCGCCCACCACAGCACGGCCUGCUGGGCAGUGUGGACCCGGGCGGUCAUCCCCAGGCCCCCAGCCCCGCGGUGACCACAGGCGUCAGAUUCCAUCCCUUCCUCCGCACUCCAGGCCUUGUCUGUCCCUCAUCCCCCUUCCUUCCCAUGCAUCCUGCCCACCGCAGCCGGGAAGUGAUGGCUUCUAGGAAUGGGCAAUACAGCCCCAAACCUCCAGCCAAGGACACCGAAGGCUGGACAGGAGGAAAGACUAGUCCACGUCCCCACGACGGUCACCCUCAGCCCUGCACCAUGGCCGCUUCUGGGACUGGUUCCACGCAGGCCUCCGCCCCCUGCAAGCCCUUCCCCGGCCCUCCAGGCCCGUGUGCGGCCCAAACCCUGUACCAGAUCUCUUAGCCCUCUUCCACGGAUGCGCGCGCUGAGGCCCACCCUGGGUAGUGGAGCUUGAAAUUUAAAGGCCGCACGCCCCUUCGCACCUCCCAGCCCCAGGUGCCUCCCUGUGUUCAAGGGAGCCGACGGCUCAGACCAGGAGCUGUGCUCGCCGCCCACCCAGCCCAUUCCGGGCUAGCCGCCAGGGUUGGCGCAGGCCUGCCAGGCGCCCCCACCUCGCCUGCAGGACGGGCCCCCCAGAAUGGAACACGAGGGGGUGGUCUCUUGCUGGGCUCCAGGGAACCCCAAAGCCGAGGCCCCCCGGCCCAUAAACAUUUACUAGGUUGUGGAGGGCUGACGUCACUCCCACCCCACACACAAGAGGGCCCCCGUCUGGAACAUCGGUCCCAGCAGGCUCCCUGAGGGGCUGUGGGGGACCCUUCCUGAGUUUACCUUGAACUUCAUGGAGCCCUUCCCAGCCCCAGGCAGUCAGGGCUGGAACUGAGGAGGGGCAGAGCCUCCCUGGGGAGCUAGGAGGGCUUCCUAGAGGAGGAGGCGGCACAGCAGAGAGGGCCCAAGGAUGAAGAGGCUUUUCCAUGUGUACCCAGCGGGAGGCUGGUCCAGGCAGAGCACACAGCAACAGCAGAGGCCUGCUGUGAGGGAGAGCAGUGGGCGAUCAGGGGCCUCCUGGUCCAGGAGAGGUGCCUGGGGGCUGCAGGGCACACACUUGCUUCCCGAGAAUCCAUCCCUGGAGACACAUCCCCAGCAGAGACAAGGCUCCAAGAACACCGGCCUGGCCCUGCGCCGUGGCUCAGGCCUGUAAUCCCAGUACUUUGGGAGGCCGAGGCUGGGGGAUCACUUGAGGUCAGGAGUUUCAGACCACCCUGGCCAACACAGUGAAACCCUGUCUCUACUAUACAAAAAUAAGCCAGGUGUGGUGGCAGGCACCUGUAAUCCCAGCUACUUGGGAGGCUGAGGCAUGAGAAUCCCUUGAACCUGGGAGGUGGAGGUUGCAGUGAGCCGAGAUCAUGUCACUGUACUCCAGCCUGGGAGACAGUGAGCGAGACUUUGUAUCAAAAAUAAAUAAAUAAAUAACGCUGGCCUGGGCUGGCGCUGACCCAG